GACCCGAGACACGGGAGCGCUUGGCACGCGGAGCCAGAGCCGGAGCUGCAGCCGCAGCGGGAGCCGGGGGAGCUCAGGGGCCGCAGGAGCCGGGCCGGAGUGAGCGCACCUCGCGGGGCCCUCGGGGCAGGUGGGUGAGCGCCACCCGGAGUCCCGCGCGCAACUUUCAGGGCGCACUCGGCGGGGCGGCUGCGCGGCUGCCGGGACUCGGCGCGGGACUGCAUGGAGGCCAAGGAGAAGCAGCAUCUGUUGGACGCCAGGCCGGCAAUCCGGUCAUACACGGGAUCUCUGUGGCAGGAAGGGGCUGGCUGGAUUCCUCUGCCCCGACCUGGCCUGGACUUGCAGGCCAUUGAGCUGGCUGCCCAGAGCAACCAUCACUGCCAUGCUCAGAAGGGUCCUGACAGUCACUGUGACCCCAAGAAGGGGAAGGCCCAGCGCCAGCUGUAUGUAGCCUCUGCCAUCUGCCUGUUGUUCAUGAUCGGAGAAGUCGUUGGUGGGUACCUGGCACACAGCUUGGCUGUCAUGACUGACGCAGCACACCUGCUCACUGACUUUGCCAGCAUGCUCAUCAGCCUCUUCUCCCUCUGGAUGUCCUCCCGGCCAGCCACCAAGACCAUGAACUUUGGCUGGCAGAGAGCUGAGAUCUUGGGAGCCCUGGUCUCUGUACUGUCCAUCUGGGUCGUGACGGGGGUACUGGUGUACCUGGCUGUGGAGCGGCUGAUCUCUGGGGACUAUGAAAUUGACGGGGGGACCAUGCUGAUCACGUCGGGCUGCGCUGUGGCUGUGAACAUCAUAAUGGGGUUGACCCUUCACCAGUCUGGCCAUGGGCACAGCCACGGCACCACCAACCAGCAGGAGGAGAACCCCAGCGUCCGAGCUGCCUUCAUCCAUGUGAUCGGCGACUUUAUGCAGAGCAUGGGUGUCCUAGUGGCAGCCUAUAUUUUAUACUUCAAGCCAGAAUACAAGUAUGUAGACCCCAUCUGCACCUUCGUCUUCUCCAUCCUGGUCCUGGGGACAACCUUGACCAUCCUGAGAGAUGUGAUCCUGGUGUUGAUGGAAGGGACCCCCAAGGGCGUUGACUUCACAGCUGUUCGUGAUCUGCUGCUGUCGGUGGAGGGGGUAGAAGCCCUGCACAGCCUGCAUAUCUGGGCACUGACGGUGGCCCAGCCUGUUCUGUCUGUCCACAUCGCCAUUGCUCAGAAUACAGACGCCCAGGCUGUGCUGAAGACAGCCAGCAGCCGCCUCCAAGGGAAGUUCCACUUCCACACCGUGACCAUCCAGAUCGAGGACUACUCGGAGGACAUGAAGGACUGUCAGGCAUGCCAGGGCCCCUCAGACUGACUGCUCAGCCAGGCACCAACUGGGGCAUGAACAGGACCUGCAGGUGGCUGGACUGAGUGUCCCCCAGGCCCAGCCAGGACUUUGCCUACCCCAGCUGUGUUGUAAACCAGGUCCCCCUCCUGACCUCUGCCCCACUCCAGGAAUGGAGCUCUUCCCAGCCUCCCAUCUGACUACAGCCAGGGUGGGGACUCAGCGGGUAUAAAGCUAGUGUGACCCUGCUCUUCCAGCUCCUGGGCCAGCUCUGGAAGGGCUGUAUUUGGGCCUAAUCCUCAGCAAAUGUUCUACCACUCGCAGGGGCAAAGGUGGUGAGCCACGGGACGUCCAAGGGGAGGCUGGCCCCAGCGCGCCCAUACUGCCUGCCUCAUGCCCCAUUCUCAGCCUGGCUGGCCUUUGCCUUUAUGAAUCUGAGCCCCUCCAUCUGCCUAUAGCAAUAGGCACGGGGGUGAGGACCCUCACACUCUCAUUUGAGCCUCCCUGAGGCAGGGAGCCAGGAGGCACCUGAGGCCUAUCUGUGCCUUAGUCACUUCAGCUAUGAGCCAAAUGUUCCCUUUCCUGGAGGGGAGAGGCUUCUUACUAGGUAAGAGACAGGUUUCCUCUUUCCUUAUUUCCUCAGCUGUGCCAACACAAAAAACAACUUUGGCACAGGUGGUGGGCAGGGGGUAGAGAGAUUUCAGCUUGGGUUCUGCACUAACAGCCUCCAAGCCCCCUGGCACUUCUGUUGCCCUGAGAGUGUCCCAGGGGAUUCAGAGUCUCCAGAAAGAUAUGGCUGGGCCAACUCUGUUGCCUACCUGGCCUGACCCAGUCGGAGCCUGACAUGGUGGAGGGAAAGGGAGACAAGUGGGGCUGCACUCGGUCCAGAGGCCAGCUAGGAGGGAAACCGCAGCUUCCUGGGGCUUGUGUGUGAAGAUUCCUGACUUAGGGGUGGCUUUUGUUUACAAGAUGCAAGAGGGGAAACCUGUCCCCGACUCAUCGAGACAACAUGCCCAGUUAUCAGGGAGUCCUGUGUCACAAGGUCUGUCUCUGCCAUUGUAAGCAAGUGCCUUGGGCGAGCUGGCCUCUGCCCCACAGUCUCAUCUGUACACCGACAGGGUUGAUGCCUCCCUCACAGGGUUGAGAACAAGAGCCAGUUGGCCAAGUACCUGUGGUUGUUGAAGAUUGGUUACUUUUACCAUCCUGGGGACAGGGAACUCUGUGGCCCGAGGCUGCCUCACUGAGGAGUCAGGUGGGCUUCCCAGCCUCCCCAGGGGCAGUGCUGAGUUUGUCUUGACUGUUCUGGCCCAAGGUGGGAGGAGGUGGGUUUGGUCACUUGCCUCCCACUUUAAAUCUCUGUCUUUCCAUCUGUGAAAUGACCUCUUUGUGCCUUCCCAGCACUGUCAUCCUGAUCGCCUGUGUUCUAGGUAGGUGGGUCCUUCAGCCCCUCCAGGUCUGUGAAAAGUCUGUGGAAAGCACUGGCCUGGAGAGGGGUGGGGGGUUGCUGGUGGGUGCUCCAUUCCACCACAAUCUCAGGGGACUCAACCUCCCCUACCCAACUCCCCACCCCCACCCAAGCCAUGGCAGGCCCCAGGAACUUGAUCCUGGGCUUUGCCGUAUGCCAAGUCCUUACACCCCUCUCAAGAGACAGUCAUUGGCUGGGCACGGUGGCUCAUGCCUGCAAUCCCAGCACCUUGGGAGGCUGAGGCAGGCAGAUGACUUGAGGCCAGGAGUUCGAGACCAGCCUGGCCAAUAUGGCGAAACCUCAUUUCUACUAAAAAUACAAAAACUAGCCAGGCGUGGUGGCUUGUGCCUGUAAUCCCAGCUACUCGGGAGGCUGAGGCAGGAGAAUCGCUUGAACCGGGGAGGCAGAGGUUGCAGUGAGCUGAGAUCACACCACUGCACUCCAGCCUGGGUGACAGAGCGAGACUCCAGCUU